AUUUCCGACCCGGGCAAGAUGGCAGCGGCGCUGCGCGUGCGUUGUUGAGUGUUCGGGACGCCGGCCUGCAGGCGCCAUGGUCUUCCUCACCGCGCAGCUCUGGCUGCGGAAUCGCGUCACCGACCGCUACUUUCGGAUCCAGGAGGUGCUGAAGCACGCCAGGCACUUCCGGGGAAGGAAAAAUCGCUGCUACAGGUUGGCGGUCAGAACCGUGAUUCGAGCCUUUGUGAAAUGCACCAAAGCCCGAUACCUGAAGAAAAAGAACAUGAGGACCCUCUGGAUUAAUCGAAUUACAGCUGCUAGCCAGGAACAUGGACUGAAGUAUCCAGCGCUCAUUGGGAAUUUAGUUAAGGCACUUCCAGGUUGGCUUAAAGGGUUACCCUAGGCCAGCAGUCAGCUCAGUCAGGGUGGUGACCAAGGACCCUGAACAAGGUGUUUGGUUCCCCGGGCCGACAUCAGGACUGGAGUCCAGCCUCCCUGCAGAUUCCACAGGUGCUUCCCUCACCCGUGUCCACAUUUAUCCUUCAGCAUCCUGCCUGGAAGUCCUCUGCUGUGCCACCCAGAUAGGAUUCUCCUAGGCCUUCCCUCCCCCCAGGCGAGUGUGCAGCUGGGUUCUUCCUGAGCCAGCGCCGCAACCACGCGGAGCCGGAGUGUGUGUCUCACACUGACAGCAGGUUCUGAUUCAUUCUUUUUUCAGUGCCAGGUGGAGCUCAACAGGAAAGUCCUAGCGGAUCUGGCCAUCUACGAGCCAAAGACUUUCAAAUCUUUGGCUGCCUUGGCCAGUAGGAGGCGACACGAAGGAUUUGCUGCUGCCUUGGGGGAUGGGAAGGAACCUGAAGGCAUUUUUUCCAGAGUGGUGCAGUACCACUGAGGACUGUUGCUGUAUUGAUUAGGAAAAGAGACAGAGUAAUUUGCAGUUUGUUUGAUUUAUACUUUUGUUUAUCUACAACCCAAUAACAGACAUGAGGGAUGGCCCUGUCUCUCUGGGACAGAGCCUCACAGAUGAUGUCCAUGUUUUGUGUGAAUGAAACUCAAACACUCUUCA